UGCCGAAGAGGCUAUCUGGGAAGCUCAUCAUCCAGCUCAGGAAGAGAUGAAACCAGGAGGCAGGAGAAUGUCAGGCAUGACCCCACACUUGUGCAACAGCCACGUCCUGCUCCUGCCAUUAGCAUGGCUCAUCCGAGGCCCAGCCCCAGGAUCCAUACAAAGUGUGUUCCUGCUGCUGGCUUCUCAUCUGCUCUGCUUCCUAAGGGACGUAUCUGUUGCUGCGUCUGAACCCACGGUUUAUCGAAAUCCCACCAAGAUGUCCUGCCAGCAGAACCAACAGCAGUGCCAGCCCCCUCCCAAGUGUCCUAUCCCCAAGUAUCCCCCAAAAUGUCCCUCAAAGUGUGCAUCCUCAUGCCCACCUCCAAUCUCUUCCUGCUGUGGCUCCAGCUCUGGGGGCUGUGGUUGCUGCAGCUCUGAGGGAGGUGGCUGCUGCCUGAGCCACCACAGACACCAUAGGUCCCACUGCCACAGACCCAAGAGCUCCAAUUGCUAUGGCAGUGGCAGUGGCCAGCAGUCUGGGGGUUCUGGCUGCUGCUCUGGAGGGGGCUGUUGCUGACCUGGACCAGGAGCAGCACCAAAGGAAUUAGUGGGCGAAGGACCCAUUGCAGCCUGGUG